CUCGAGAGGAGCCCGUGGGCUGCUGGACCGGACCGGACAGCACCAGGAAGCCCGGCAGGGACAGUGAGCUGAUAACUGUUCCCAGGCCAUGUAGGUGGCCAGCACAGGACAGGUCACCUUCUGGCCCACAGGAACUUCUUGCCCAGGCUCAAGCUGCCCCUUCGCACAAGGGCCUCUGGGCUCUGAGACACAGACAGGACUUCGAAGCCUGUCCAGAUGAGGCAGUUGGAAUCUCCCCAGCUUGUGGGGAGAAUUCUGCCAGAUAUCAGGACAGAUGGGGAACAGCAGAAGCCGUGUGGGGCGGAGCUUUUGUUCACAGUUUCUUCCUGAGGAACAGGCAGAGAUUGAUCAAUUGUUUGAUGCUCUGUCAUCAGAUAAAAACAGCCCGAAUGUCUCAUCCAAAUCCUUCUCUCUGAAGGCACUACAGAACCACGUCGGGGAAGCUCUUCCCCCAGAGAUGGUCACCAGGCUGUAUGAUGGCAUGCGGAGGGUCGACCUGACAGGGAAGGCGAAGGGACCCAGUGAGAACGUGUCCCAGGAGCAGUUCACAGCAUCCAUGUCCCACCUGUUGAAAGGAAACUCCGAGGAGAAGAGUCUCAUGAUUAUGAAAAUGAUUUCUGCCACAGAAGGUCCCGUGAAGGCCAGAGAAGUCCAAAAGUUUACAGAGGAUCUGGUUGGCUCUGUGGUGCACGUGCUAAGCCACAGACAGGAGCUGAGAGGCUGGACUGGGAAGGAAGCCCCAGGGCCCAACCCCCGGGUGCAGGUGCUGGCUGCUCAGCUGCUCUCUGACAUGAAGCUGCAAGAUGGCAAGAGACUUCUGGGGCCCCAGUGGCUGGACUAUGACUGUGACCGAGCUGUGAUCGAGGACUGGGUGUUCAGGGUCCCCCAUGUGGCCAUAUUCCUGAGUGUGGUCAUUUGCAAGGGCUUUCUCAUCCUGUGCUCGUCUCUUGAUCUGACUACCCUGGUCCCUGAGCGUCAAGUGGACCAGGGCAGGGGUUUUGAGAGCAUCCUGGAUGUCCUCUCUGUCAUGUACAUCAACGCCCAGCUGCCUCGGGAGCAGCGGCACCGCUGGUGCCUGCUCUUUUCGUCUGAGCUCCAUGGACACAGCUUCUCCCAGCUCUGUGGCCACAUCACUCACCGGGGACCCUGUGUGGCUGUCCUCGAGGACCAUGACAAGCAUGUGUUCGGUGGGUUUGCCUCUUGCUCUUGGGAGGUGAAGCCUCAGUUUCAAGGGGACAACAGAUGCUUCCUGUUCUCCAUCUGCCCCAGCAUGGCUGUGUACACACACACGGGCUACAACGACCACUACAUGUACUUGAACCAUGGACAGCAGACGAUCCCGAACGGACUGGGUAUGGGGGGGCAGCACAAUUACUUUGGGCUUUGGGUGGAUGUUGAUUUUGGGAAAGGACACAGCAGAGCCAAGCCCACGUGCACCACGUACAACAGCCCGCAGCUGUCGGCUCAGGAGAACUUCCAGUUUGAUAAGAUGGAGGUGUGGGCGGUUGGAGACCCCUCAGAGGAGCAGUUGGCCAAGGGCAACAAGAGCAUCCUGGAUGCGGACCCUGAGGCCCAGGCCCUGCUGGAGAUCAGUGGGCAUUCGCGCCACAGCGAAGGGCUCCGGGAAGUCCCGGACGAUGAAUGAGGAGCCGCCUGAGCCUUCCUGGAGCCAGGACCUGGAUUCCUCUGGGUAGAGGGCAACGCCUGCAGCCCCUCUUCCCUCCCACAUGGUUUAACUGUAAUAGCGUACCGCACGGGUCACAGCCUGGUAGUCCCACAUGUGCCAAGAAGACGCCCUCUGAAGCCAUGUCCUGACUCAUGGGUGGAUCUCCCAGAAAUAGAUGUUUUUUAAGUUUUCUUUUUUUCCCUACAGGGUCACCCUCAGGAUCUCUCCAAGAAAUCUUGUGUCAAAUUAGUAACUCAGUCUUAUACUUUGUUCUUUUUUACCAACGAAAUCCUAAGCAGCUGAGACCUUUCAGACCCCCGCUGGCAUUAGGGAAUUCCGCUGGCAUUAGGGAAUUCCGCUGGCAUUAGGGAAUUCCGCUGGCAUUAGGGAAUUCCGCUGGCAUUAGGGAAUUCCGCUGGCAUUAGGGAAUUCCGCUGGCAUUAGGGAAUUCCGCUGGCAUUAGGGAAUUCCGCUGGCAUUAGGGAAUUCCGCUGGCAUUAGCAUUGCUGGGAUCUCAACUUCUCUAUUGAGGAGGGGGUUCCUCCCGCUGGGGUUCAUAUGGCCUCACUCAGGCCAUCCCUGUUAGAAGGUGGUACCUGAUGGUCUGUUCUGACGGGUGAGGGACAGAGGCAUCUGGAUGAAAAUCUCGACGCUUUCUGGGAACAGCUUCCAAUGGCAUGGGAGUUCUGUAUUUAAAAGCAUGAACUGUGUAUAAAAUGGGGAAAUGGAGGCAGGAGACUUUGAGGUAACAUGGUCUGGUGGUGGCAUGAGUCCUCAGAAGGUAUUUGUAAUAAGGUUCCACACCCAGCUCUCUCAGCUGUUUUUAAAUGAAUGUGUGUGAGGAACAGAUGGGAAAGUUGGGAGAUCUGUCUACAGAGAAGCAAAGUUGUGGUUCUCUUGCUAACUUCAAGGUGAGGGACAUUGGGCACCCUAAGUUUGGGAACUUGGUUGAUAAAUACGUAUAUGGUCCAUUCCAUAAAUCAGUGGUGAGUGACUGGCCUGGGUUCUAGACCUCUGGGAACCAGCACCUGAGUCACAGCUGUCUAGGCCUCGGUGCUGGCCUGGGUUCUAGAUCUCUGGGAACCAGUGCCUGAGUCACAGCUGUCAGUGCAGCCAUUUGCCCAGGGCUGCUCCCGAGGGGGAUGAUGGGAAAUUCAGCAGUGUAGACUGACUUUAAACAAGCUCCGGUGAUCCUGAAAUGCUGAAGAUCGUGUAGGUGGGUUGUGGGGUCAGCAGAGCUGCCAUCUGCCCACGUCUGGAAAACAACACACGGUGAGUCACCGGUUGGCCAUGAGAUCUCCCCACUUAAAGGUGCUGUGAGCUUGUCUCUAAGAUAUAUACCUCUUCCUUUUGUCUUUUGCUGUAAGCUUUGACCUUUUGCAGAUCUGAUGAAAAUACAACCUCUUAUUGUAUAGUUUGCCUUGAUUAUAAGCCAUAGUAAAUCGAGCUGUUCGCAUUUUUGCAGGCCUUGCAUUUUCUACUGGGAGGUUCAUCAAACCUUCCACUUAGCAAUAGCCCUGACUCAGGCAGAAUGCCUCAUAAAUUAGCCUUCGAAAGAAAAGUGCACGCUCAGACAGUGUGUGGAGGGGCAGGAGCGUGAUGCAGACAAGGACUUAGUCAUGACUGAUUUUCCUUAGCCAGUUUGUAAUGGCUUAUGGGGAACAUUGUGAGCUUCCUACCUGACAUGUUGGCAGAAGUAGAAUAUUAGGAUCCUCAAGCAUCUCUACCGUAAGUCCAAAGAAUUUAGGUCCCUAUUGUCACUUUGUUUUGCAAUGUUUUUUAUAAAAAUGCAAUUAAAUACCUCACUAUUAAACUGCCAUGAUGCCUCAGUUAAAAAAAAAAUUAAAUGUCCGUCAGUGUCUGUGCCUUGGUGACCAUUGAUUGCUGCUUCUGCCCAGGCCGCUGCAAAGGUUAGGACUUUGUCCACUCACAUGCUUUCCACCCUGAGCUUGUUCUAAGGAGAGUGCAGAUCACGAAUGCACCUGCUUCCAGGCAGUGCACUUAGAGAAAGGUCACUGGCCCGGGCUUGGGAGCCUGGGGGAUGCAGCUCUCUCUGUGGGCUUCUCUUGGUGCACGGUUCUGCCUCUGGACACUCAAACCUUUUUAGGGCGUGUGCAGGGCUGGGGCCAGUGGACCUGACAGUACCUUACCUGGCUCUGAGAAACUCGCAAUCCUAGUUUGCACAAAUGAAUAGUUUGUUCUUUUGUGAAACCAGAAUGAGAAUUCAGGUUCUAAGGACUAGAGGUCUCCCUACAAAUGAAGACUUAUCAGGGCCCUAGAAAGUGCUAGGAGGAAGGGGUUAAAAAAAAAAUUUGUCCGCGUUGCAAACUAUUAUAAAUGAUUGCCACAUUGCAAGCUAUUAUUUUCUCCCACCAUAUUUUUUAAUUAAAAAAAAGUCUGGGGCCGGGUGCGGUGGCUCACGCCUGUAAUCCCAGCACUUUGGGAGGCCGAGGUAGGCGGAUCACCUGAGGUCGGAAGUUCGAGACCAGCCUGACCAACAUGGAGAAACCCCAUCUCUACUAAAAAUACAAAAUUAGCUGGGCAUGGUGGCACAUGCCUGUAAUCUCAGCUACUCAGGAGGCUGAGGUAGUAGAAUUGCUUGAACCAGGGAGGCAGAGGUUGUGGUGAGCCGAGAUCGUGCCAUUGCACUCUAGCCUGGGCAACAAGAGUGAAACUCCGUUUCAAGAAAAAAAAAAAGGCUGGGUGUGAUGGCUCACGCCUGUAAUCCCAGCAUUUUGGGAGCUUGAGGCAGGCCGAUUGCUUGAGCCCAGGAGUUCAAGACCAGCCUGGGCAACAUGGCGAAAACCCAUCUCUACAAAAAAAAAUACGAAAAUUAACCAGGCAUGGUAACACAUGCCUGUGGUCCUAGCUACUUGGGAGGCUGAGGUGUGAGGAUCAUUUAGGCCUGGAAGGUUGAGGCUGCUAUAAGCUGUGAUUGUGCCACUGCACUCCAGCCUGGGCAACACAGCAAGACCCUAUGUUUAAAAAAAAUUGUGUACCUGGUUUAGAAAAAAAAGAUAAAAGGAUACAACUUAAAGUCAGUCAUCUUCCUGCCUCUUCUCCAGCUAUUUUCCCUCCUGACAGGCAAAGGCACUGAUGCAAAAAUCACUCAGGUCUCCUCCCUGUGACUUGGUGCACACCUGGGCAUCACUGUCUUUUACACACUGAUGUGUCCCUCGCUUUCUUUUUUAAAGGGAGGUCCGUAACCACCCACCUGCCUCCCUCUUGUCUUUAUGGACUGCGUGAUGUCCCACCAUAUGGAUGCUCUCGGGCCUAGCGUUCCACCGUCUGCAGCUGGGGAACAUUUUGUUUGCAGCUAAUCAUUGUCAUGAAUAUCGUUUAUGUGUGCCUUGCUGUGAUGGUGUCUGUGGGAUAAACUCUUAGAAUUGGAAUUGUUGGAUUGAGAGGUAUAUGCCUUUUAUUUAGAUAUAGAUGAAUUAAAAAAACCUCUUGAGCUCAAUUUAUACUCAAUAUACCGGGGUGCCUGUUUGCCAUGUUUUCAGCAAAACUGUAUUAAAAUAUGUUUUUUUAACCUGA